GGGUAGCUGCGGCCGCAGCAGCGGCGGCGGGCAUGGCAGAGGCGCGAUCCCAGCCCUCGGCGGGGCCGCAGCUCAACGCGCUACCGGACCACUCUCCGUUGCUGCAGCCGGGCCUGGCGGCGCUGCGGCGCCGGGCCCGGGAAGCUGGCGUCCCGCUCGCGCCGCUGCCGCUCACCGACUCCUUCCUGCUGCGGUUCCUGCGCGCCCGGGAUUUCGAUCUGGACCUGGCCUGGCGGUUACUAAAAAACUAUUAUAAGUGGAGAGCAGAAUGUCCAGAAAUAAGUGCAGAUCUACACCCUAGAAGUAUUAUUGGCCUCCUAAAGGCUGGCUACCAUGGAGUCCUGAGAUCCAGGGAUCCCACUGGCAGCAAAGUUCUUAUUUACAGAAUCGCACACUGGGACCCCAAAGUUUUUACAGCUUAUGACGUAUUUCGAGUAAGUCUAAUCACAUCCGAGCUUAUUGUACAGGAGGUAGAAACUCAGCGGAAUGGAAUCAAGGCUAUCUUUGAUCUGGAAGGUUGGCAGUUUUCUCAUGCUUUUCAAAUCACUCCAUCCGUAGCCAAGAAGAUUGCUGCUGUACUUACGGAUUCAUUUCCAUUGAAAGUUCGUGGCAUCCAUUUGAUAAAUGAACCAGUAAUUUUCCAUGCUGUCUUUUCCAUGAUCAAACCAUUCCUGACUGAAAAAAUUAAGGAACGGACAGGGCCUCACUUUGUGCAGUGGCACGAUCUUGGCUCACUGCAACCUCCACCUCCUGGGCUCAAGCAAUCCUCCUGCCUCAGCCCACCAAGUAUCUGGGACUACAGUCCUGCACCACCACGCCCAGCUAAUUUUUGUAUUUUUUUUGUACCAGCCAUGUUGCCCAGGCUGGUGUUGAACUCCUGAGCUCAAGUAAUCCACCUGCCUUGGCCUCUCAAAGUGUUGGGAUUACAGGCAUGAGCCACUGCACCCGGCUGUCUCUUAACUUUAUACUAACUAACAGUAUCCAUCGACUGUACCAUAUAAAUUGUUUCUCAUAGAUUUAAUUGUGUGCUCAGAUAUAUGCUUCUACUUAAUAUGAAUUAGUACCAGCUAGUACAUUUUUAUCGUGUAUAGAAUAGUCCCAAGGUAUUAGUUUGGUAAGAAUCACUUGCACAUAAGGGAAUAGAAUUUAUAAAAUAACUUUAUUUAAUCUUUAAAAAUUUACUUAUGAAAGAGGAAAAUAACUUUUUAUAAAUUUUAUGCAGUUAUAAGAAUGCAAAUCCAAGAAACAGUAAGGUUAUUAGAUCCACAGUAAUACAACCUAAACAUAAGUAAAAUUAUUAGAUUCAUAACCAGAGGAAUAAAGGAUGUGGUAUCUAUUUAUACACUCCAUUUUAGAAGUUAUUAGAAUACCUUGUUUUAUGAGGUUGAUUUUCCACUGGAAAUGCAUCUAAUGCGGUUUCCUUCUAAAGUGUUUUGGCUAUUUCAGAUUCACAUGCAUGGGAACAACUACAAACAAAGCUUGCUUCAGCAUUUCCCAGACAUUCUUCCUCUGGAAUAUGGUGGUGAAGAAUUCUCCAUGGAGGACAUUUGUCAGGAAUGGACAAAUUUUAUAAUGAAGUCUGAAGAUUAUCUCAGCAGCAUUUCUGAGAGCAUUCAAUGAGAAGUUAUGUCAUGUGAAUGGCUUCCUAACUAAAAAUACAUGAGUGAUAUCCAACCUGGUUAAAUGAAUGAAAGAAAAGGAGCAAAUCUUUUAAACUAAUGCUUGCCUGAACUUUAAAAAUGUAGAAAUCUUCUGACAUGAGCAACACAGGUGUUUGGAAAGAUUUUUUACUUUUUAAAUGCUUUUUUCUCUACUUUUGAAGUAAUUAAAUGUCAGUACAUUUUAAGAGCAUAAAAAUCGGCGAUUUUGUACUUGAAGAGAACAUGAAAGUUAUUGCUAAAGUAGCUGCUCAUGUGCAUCUUUGUAUGUUUCUAGAAAGUUAUAUUUUAAACAAGUUCUCUGAUUAAAUUGGUUUAGAAAAAAAUUUAGAAAUAUUCCGCUUAAAAAUACUAGCACAAGUCAGCUAAUGAUAAAAAAAUUAACACUUGUUUUAAGUGGAUGUCAGAUUAAAUUAUAAUUCAUUAUAAUUAAAAUCUGAAUAGAGUUUUAUGGUUAUUCCUGUGGACCAGCAAGACAUUUCAUCUCAGGGAAAUUUUAUUUUAGUAUAUUAACACGAUAGAAACUUUUUUUUUUUUUUUCAGACAGAGUCUUGCUCUGUCGCCCAGGCUAGAGUGCAGUAGUGAGAUCUCAGCUCACUGCAACCUCUGCUAGGAUUACAUGUGCACACCACCACUCCUGGCUAAGUUUUGUAUUUUAUAUAGAGAUGGGGUUUUGCCACGUUGGCCAAGCUGGUCUCAAACUCCUGAACUCAAGUAAUUUGCCUGCUUCGGCCUCCCAGAGUCCUGGGAUUACAGUCGUGAGCCAUCGCGCCUGGCCGUGAUAGAAACUUUCAGCUGAGGAGUCUAUAUGCCAUACUACUCUAUGUGGCAUCUUUAGGUCUCUGUGAAAUCAUGUUGAUGUAAUUGAUUAACAAAAAUAAUUUAGAAAAUACGUCAGGCACAGUUGAUGGCUUCUCAAUAUCUGCUUUGCAUUUUUAAACAAAUCAAGAAUGUAAUUUUAACUUUUGCUUAUGGUCAUUCUUAUGACUACACGGAAAGGGAUGGAAUCAUACUUACUUGUCUUAUACAUGGACUGUUUUUAGUUAACAAUAACGUAACUACACAAAGGAAAGGAAAUGUUUACAUUUUAAAAAAUUACUGUCAAUUACAUCUGGUAUUUUUCAGAUUAUGCAUAAAAUAAUAUGAGUUUGACUAUUGUAUCAGAAUAUUUUAAUCAAAUCCUGCAAUUUAUAUUAACUUAAAAAAACAUCUGGUAAAGACUGGGUGUGGCAGCUCACACCUGUAAUCCCAGCACUUUGGGAGGCCGAGGCUGGAUGGAUGAUUGCUUGAGCGCAGGAGUUCUAGACCAGCCUGGGCAAUACAGGGAGACCCUGUCUCUAUUUCAAAAAUAAAUAAAUAGGCCCCGGUGUGUGAUGUUCCCCUUCCUGUGUCCAUGUGUUCUCAAAAAAAAUUAAAAAAUAAAAAUAAAAAUAAAUAAAUAAAUAACCGGUAAAGAUGUACUGUUUCUACUGCAGUUUAUAAUAUUUCAUUUAUUAAGAAAGAUAUCAUCUCAGCUUUCAAAUUCAACAUAGCCCUCAAUUUAUGACAUAAGUUUUAUACUUAGUAUUUUAUAAUUUCUUAAUUUUGUUAUAAACUUGAAAAUGUAGAAUAUGGGGUCCAAAAUCUGUUGAACAUUUGUUCAGCUAGUUAGGUUUCAACAUUAAUCAUAUACAUUAAUAGUAUCUUUAUGUAAGGAUAUGUGAAGGGUGUUUUUCUUUAUAAGAAAAUUAGUUUAAUCAGGUGAGCUGAUACUUAGGAUUAUACAUAUAUCUAUGAUAAAAUUGAAAGUAAUUGUGGUUGUUCUUUAGAGAACGUGUUUUGAUUUUGACUUAGUAUUGGGAAGCUAACAACAUUAUAAUUUUUAUUAAAAAACUGGACCCUGGGCCGGGCGCGGUGGCUCACGCCUGUAAUCCCAGCACUUUGGGAGGCCGAGGCGGGCGGAUCACGAGGUCAGGAGAUCGAGACCAUCCCGGCUAAAACGGUGAAACCCCGUCUCUACUAAAAAUACAAAAAAAUUAGCCGGGCGUAGUGGCGGGCGCCUGUAGUCCCAGCUACUUGGGAGGCUGAGGCAGGAGAAUGGCGUGAACCCGGGAGGCGGAGCUUGCAGUGAGCCGAGAUCCCGCCACUGCACUCCAGCCUGGGUGACAGAGCGAGACUCCGUCUCAAAAAAAAAAAAAAAAAAAAAAAAAAAAACUGGACCCUGCCUGUUUUCUAAAAAACACUUUAAAGUAUUUUAAAAUAAAAGCAUACUAUUUAAAAUUGUAUAAUUAAAAAUAAUAAAAGAACAAAAUCACUUAAAAAGAAUAAACAGUGUCAAUAACAAAAAACCUCUGGCUUACCCAACUUUUGUUUCUAGAAGAUUUAUAUCAAUCACCAGUUCCACUUCAUUUAUUUUUGUUUAUUUCAAACACUUUCUUAUGACUCUGUGGAGGAGUGAUUAGUUUAGUACCCAAAUAAAGGAUAACAUUUUAAAAUGUCCUUUAAAUUAGAUUUUUUUGGUGAUAGGUUCCAUAGUAAAUAGAAUUAAGAUAAGUCAGUUAAUCUAGGCAUAUUUUAUGAUGGAACUUUGAAGUGUUUAUAAAUGAAACAAUUCACUGAAGAACAUUAAAAGAAAAUUGAAAUGAAUGGUCAAAUUAAUAAAGUGUCAAAGCAAAUAAUUGUCUAAUUGUCUAUAUUACUUUAGUGAUUAUGCCAGAAGUGCCUUUUAAAAGGUUAACUGUAUUAUGUGCUCAUUGUGUUACUCAACUGCACGUAAUUUAUUUGUUUUAAUAUUGUUUGAAAGAAAAUAAACAUCUUUCACAUAAA